GAGGACUUCUGGUCUGUUCGGUACUUGAACUGCCAGCAAAUUUCAACUCCCGCUUGCCAUUCAACAUCAUGGAUGAUCCGAAGAGUGAACAGCAGCGCAUACUGCGCCGCCACCAACGCGAGAGGCAGGAGCUGCAGGCCCAGAUCCGGAGCUUAAAAAACUCGGUCCCCAAGACCGACAAGACGAAAAGAAAGCAGUUGCUCCAAGACGUGGCCCGCAUGGAGGCCGAGAUGGCUCAGAAGCACCGGCAGGAGCUGGAGAAGUUCCAAGACGACAGUAGCAUUGAAUCUGUCGUCGAAGACCUGGCCAAGAUGAAUCUGGAAAACCGGCCUCCCCGCUCCUCCAAAGCCCACAGAAAGAGAGAAAGAAUGGAGUCCGAGGAGAGGGAGCGCCAGGAGAGCAUCUUCCAGGCUGAGAUGUCGGAGCACCUGGCCGGCUUCAAGCGCGAGGAGGAGGAGAAGCUCGCCGCCAUCCUGGGAGCCAGGGGUCUGGAGAUGAAAGCGAUCCCGGCCGACGGCCACUGCAUGUACCGCGCCAUCCAAGACCAGCUGGUGUUCAGCGUGUCUGUGGAGAUGCUGCGCUGCCGCACCGCCAGCUACAUGAAGAAGCACGUCGACGAGUUCCUGCCCUUCUUCAGCAACCCCGAGACCAGCGACUCCUUCGGCUACGACGACUUCAUGAUCUACUGCGACAACAUCGUGCGCACCACGGCAUGGGGAGGCCAGCUGGAGCUGAGGGCCCUGUCGCACGUCCUGAAGACCCCCAUCGAGGUGAUCCAGGCCGACUCGCCCACCUUGAUCAUCGGGGAGGAGUACGUCAAGAAGCCGAUCAUCCUGGUCUACCUGCGCUAUGCCUACAGCCUCGGCGAGCACUACAACUCCGUGACACCGCUCGAGGCCGGCGCCGCCGGGGGCGUGCUCCCGCGUCUCCUGUAGGCCCCAAGGCGCUGAGCAGCCCCGGGAAACUGUCGCCGUCGCCGCAUCUCCUCAGUAGGCUCAGUUUAUUUUCCCCUUUUGCUUUUCUCUGUUUUUCUUUUCCUUCCUUUUAAUCAAAACUACCCGCCCCCGCCCCGCCCCCGCUUUCCUAACCUUGCUGCUUUCACAGGGUGGGAAACGAAAUUCGAGGGAAAUUCCCCGGAAAUAUGAGGGAAAUCUCUGCAUUGCACCACCAGAGGGGCAUAAAUUUGAAAGUUCUAACCUCUUCUUGCCCUUAAGGGUCUUUUACCUCCCUCACCAACUAAGAUUUGGUCAUGUUGCGUAUAACUUCACCACAAAAAUGGAAAUAUUGGCCGGGCGCGGUGGCUCACGCCUGUAAUCCCAGCACUUUGGGAGGCCGAGGCGGGCGGAUCACGAGGUCAGGAGUUCGAGACCAGCCUGGCCAACAUGGUGAAACCCCACCUCUACAAAAAAUACAAAAAUUAGCCGGGCGUGGUGGCAGGCACCUGUAGUCCCAGAUACUCGGGAGGCUAAGGCAGGAGAAUCGCUUGACGGGAAGCGGAGGUUGCAGUGAGCCGAGAUCGUGCCUUUGCACUCCAGCGUGGAAGACAGUGAGACUCCGUCUCAAAAAAAUGAAAAAUUAGCCAGGCAGGUUGGCGGGGGCCUGUAAUCCUAGCUACUUGGGGUGCUGAGGCAGGAGAAUCAACUGAACCCGGGAGGCGGAGGCUGCAGUGGGCCGGGAUCGUACUACUGCACUCCAGCAUGGAAGACAGCGAGACUCCGUCUCC